GAUAAACACGGUUCGCCCCGCCUGCAGUAUUGGGGCGAUGCUGUCCUGGAAGAACGGGCUUUCUGAAUGUGACCUCGGGAUGCUGCAGCGGCGCAAUGCUGCUACUGCUGAAUGAGUAGCUCUCCUGCCACCGCAGGGCGACUGCGGUGGGCACAGCAGGGCGCACAGAGGAGGGGGUAAUCUGCCCACCCAGGCUAAGGAUUUGAGGGUUCUGACAAAAAAGAGCUGGUUGAGGAUGACACAGUUGUGAACUAACCUGGCUCCUACUACCCCACAGGGCAGCCAGGUCCCAGUAGUCUUGGGUACCACUGCCCCCACCAUACCACCAUUGUAAAGUAUGGACUCCUGCUUAGCCAACGUGCAGCUCUAGGCAGGAUCUCUGAAGGAUGCUCUGGCACACAGAUGGUGCAGGUAUGACUUUACCUGCACACAAGCUUACAUGUGCCCUGUCAUAUAUGGCUACACGUUUCCCCAUUUCCCCACAGUCUUCCUAUUUAACUGGUCUUCAAUCCUCCUUUCUAGGGCUUUCCGCCUGCACACAGUCAUUUGGAGAAAAUCAAGUGAGUGCACUUCUCCCCACAGAGGAUUCUGUAUGUUAUGUAACACACUCACACUGGGAUUCCUCAAGUUACCAUUUUGCCCCAACUCAGCCAGCACUUGGUUUUCUGGCGGGGGUGUCAGGAUGAUGCAAAUGGAGGUGGAAGCUUCAUUCCCUGGGGGCUUUUAUUCCCCUCCUUGAAGCCCCAGUUCAAGGCCCAGGAACAAAGGGGAAAGUGUGCAAUGUUCCAGCCGACUUAAUGGGCUUGCCUUAUGCGGAGAGGCAGUCCUGCAGGACAGAGCUAAUGUGUGGUCUCCCAGGAAGCUCAUCAGAACACCUCUUGUCCCUUUUCUUUAAAAGAAAAAAAAUUUAAAAAGUUUUUGCUUCCAUCUCAAUGUCCAUUCCAUUAUUUUGUAGCUACAAUAAAGAAACAUGGGCAGCAGUGAUCAUUCUUUUUGUCCUAUGUAAUCAUGUCUAGUGUUAGGACCUUACAAAGCUCCAGACAUACCUCAGGUGUAUUCUGCACUUUUCAUAUUUAUUCACUGCUCACUGGGUCACACAGAUGAUUCACACUUGAUUCCACCUUCCUCUGGACAACUCUCCCUCAAACAACACCCCUCUAUCAACUUAUAGGGAAAGGAGAUUCACUUAGAGAAAACUUCUUGAAUUAAAGACCAGACUCAGUUUCGCCAGGUAACUAAUCCUGGCAUACCGGUGACUAGGAAGUCAUCACCUAACACUCUACCUAGAUAUAAACUCUCAGGAAGGAGGCAGGCCGGUGGGGACAUUUCCACAGACAUUUCUAAAACUGUGGCAAUUGAGUAUAUUUUACAGAUACAAUUUUGGUAGAUUCCCAUCCAGCUUAAGACAUUUAAAAUGCAAUUUUGUUCACACGCAUGUGCGCGCACACAGACACACACGCACGUGUCAACUAGGGUGAUAUUAACAGUCCAUUUCCACUGGGCAAUUCUGUGACAGCAACUACAACUAACAAACUUCUUUUCUGAAGAGUAAAAAAGAAAACAAAAGCCUCUCCAUCUAUUUUAAAAGGUUAUUUUAUAUUGUUUAGCAUUCUUUCGAAACAGGAAUUGGCUGGACACUUCUCCCUUUUCAAAGAUCAGGUAAACUACUCUCCCACCCACCUCCUCCCCAAGACCAAGCCAUUUUUUAAAGCAAAAAUUCUGUUUCCAAAGGAAGAAAAAUGAACAAAUUCCAUUAAUGAAUUACAUACAUGGAAUGUGGCUUGUCUAGGACAUUUGUAUUUGUAAAUAAAUGGCUCCCUGUUUAUUAUGUAUGUUUUACUGGAAAAAAAACCAACUCUAAUGCCUCUGAGCAUGUUAUAAUACAGCAAAUAUUUCCACUUAUGGUUUCAGUUCCACUGUUUCUUGGUACUCACUAGAAAGAAAUCGGGUUACAUGGAGUCAGUUGUGGGGUUUAAGCGUCCAGGCUGACUUGGGGACGCGGCACCUCUAAAGUUCUCAUGUUUGCCAAAGUGCGGGGGGAAGGGGGAAUGGCUCCUAGGAAUCUUAUGGGGAUUAAUCUGGGGUUUCGCCUUUGUCCCGGGAUCUUUCUAAGGCUCACCACGGCCUCCGUCUGCAGCUUCAGAAGCGAAGCCGGCGUGCGAUCUCCUUGGCGGGCGGACUGGGCACAGUCCCUGCCUUGCCCUGCUGCCGGCGCCCGCACACCGCGGUCUCAGGAUCUCCCCGCAGGCCUAGGCCUGCAGUCCUCGGGCGGAGACGGGGCCUGGGGGAGCGACCCUCACCGGGCCAGGCACAGGCAGUUUACCCUGGUGCCUGUAGGGUGCUCGAGUUUCCCACACGCGGGAAGCGGAGGCGUGGGCCAAGCGCCGGGGGCUGCCCAAGAACUCCACCGCCCCGUGCGGCGCGCAGGGCCUGGCGGCGCGAAACUUCCACAAAGCCGCCGGCCGCCUCCGGCCUUGCCUCCACUCCGCAGUCCCAGCUGCCUAGACCUCGGUGUCUUCCCAGACAAUGAGCCCUGCCAGUGCACUAGGCUGUUCCGCUCUGACUUCUUCUGCCCGCACAUGGGGACCCGAGCGAAAGGUUAUGGGUUGGAACAAGUCAGCGCAUCUCCUUCCACGCGCCGCAUCCUUCGGGAAGACAAACAGAGUACGCCCCCCACCUCAAUUUCGGGCCCUGGUCUGUGGGCUGGGCCACAGUCCGGGAAGACCCAAGGGGUCACGGGUCCAGAUCCGUCUUUACUUUGUCCUCCGCUCCAGGGCUCCAGGGCCCUGGGCAGCAGAGAGGUGGAUUUCAGAGAAAGCCCGGGUCAGCCAGGCCUUGAACUCAGCCCCUCUGAACUCCACCGUCAGCAGCGUGGGCGGCAACUCAAUUCUCCUGGGAGGAGGCUGCACCCCCAGAACGGAAAAUCCGCAAACGUCGCGCAGAGACCCACAGGCAUUUCUACCUUUCCUUCCACAAGCCCUGCAGAAAGUUAUCGCCAGAACCUCUGGAACCUGAGCCGACUCCAGCCUCCAGCAACUCCCUCAACCUUCCAGGGAAACUUUCAGAAGUUUCCCUUUCCUUCGCUCCUCAAUUCCUUGGACUUUCUCCAGCCCCCAGGUUUGCUCAUUACUCUGCUGACUGCCCUUUAG